GCGGGGCCGGUAGGAUCGCGUCGGGAGCCGGUACCGAGGCCCGAGCCGCGGGAGUCGAGCGAAGGCAGCGCCGAGGCCGCGGUUUCCCCCUGGGCCUCCCCAGCAGCAGCCAUGGGCAUCAAAUUUUUAGAAGUUAUCAAACCAUUCUGUGCAGUUCUACCAGAAAUUCAGAAACCGGAAAGGAAAAUCCAGUUUAGAGAGAAGGUUCUGUGGACUGCUAUAACGCUCUUCAUUUUCUUAGUGUGUUGUCAGAUCCCACUGUUUGGAAUCAUGUCAUCAGAUUCUGCAGAUCCUUUCUACUGGAUGAGAGUUAUUCUGGCUUCCAAUAGAGGAACUUUAAUGGAAUUGGGUAUCUCCCCAAUUGUAACAUCUGGUUUGAUUAUGCAGUUGUUAGCUGGAGCCAAAAUCAUUGAAGUUGGAGAUACACCGAAAGAUAGAGCUUUAUUCAAUGGAGCCCAGAAACUGUUUGGUAUGAUCAUUACCAUUGGGCAAGCCAUUGUGUAUGUCAUGACGGGGAUGUAUGGGGACCCUGCAGAAAUGGGUGCCGGAAUCUGUCUCCUGAUCAUCAUUCAGUUGUUUGUUGCUGGUUUGAUUGUGCUGCUGUUAGAUGAGCUGCUACAGAAGGGUUACGGCUUGGGGUCUGGGAUUUCCCUCUUUAUUGCCACCAACAUCUGUGAGACCAUUGUCUGGAAGGCCUUUAGUCCCACUACCAUUAACACUGGCAGAGGUACUGAGUUUGAGGGUGCAGUCAUAGCUCUGUUCCAUUUGUUGGCCACCAGGACGGACAAAGUCCGAGCUUUACGGGAGGCUUUUUAUCGGCAGAACUUACCCAAUCUCAUGAACCUCAUUGCUACAGUUUUUGUGUUUGCUGUUGUUAUAUAUUUCCAAGGAUUUCGCGUUGAUCUGCCCAUUAAGUCGGCCCGUUACCGAGGACAGUACAGCAGCUACCCCAUCAAACUCUUCUACACCUCCAACAUCCCCAUCAUCCUCCAGUCGGCCCUGGUGUCCAACCUGUAUGUUAUUUCCCAGAUGCUGUCUGUUCGAUUUAGUGGCAACUUUUUAGUAAAUUUACUAGGACAGUGGGCCGAUGUCAGUGGGGGAGGACCCGCACGUUCUUACCCAGUUGGAGGCCUUUGUUACUAUCUUUCUCCUCCUGAGUCCAUGGGCGCCAUCUUUGAGGAUCCUGUCCAUGUCGUUGUUUAUAUCAUCUUCAUGUUGGGGUCAUGUGCAUUCUUCUCUAAGACAUGGAUUGAAGUGUCUGGUUCCUCAGCCAAAGAUGUAGCUAAACAGCUGAAAGAACAGCAGAUGGUAAUGAGGGGCCACCGAGAUACCUCUAUGGUUCAUGAGCUUAAUAGGUACAUCCCCACCGCAGCUGCGUUUGGCGGUUUGUGCAUUGGCGCCCUGUCAGUGCUGGCUGACUUCCUGGGGGCCAUUGGAUCUGGCACUGGAAUUCUGCUAGCAGUCACUAUUAUUUACCAGUAUUUUGAAAUAUUUGUUAAAGAACAGGCCGAAGUUGGUGGGAUGGGUGCUUUGUUUUUCUAAAUGUUCAAAUAUUUCAUUUUGUGCGUGUGAAAGGGAAAACACUUUGACGGAUCGUUUUUGUCAGAUGACACUGGUGGCUCCCCUUUUCUCCCCUCACAGUUUCUUGUUUCGAGUGCUGACUGACCCGUUUCUGAAAUGGGCACCGAGCUAAGUCUGUGUGCAGCAUUAGUACCCGCUGCCUUAAAACUCAAGUUUACAUUAUUCAUUAAAAAAAGUACAUCUAGUGUUGCCUGUAAUGCUGGAAACCAGUGUAUCUACCUUGCUGUGUUAAAUCAUGACAGUGAGACGGUGAGAUGGAUUCGUUUUGCACACAACAUUCAAAACACUUCAUAUUGCCCCCACUUGUUGAAAAAUAAAUGUAGUUCAAAUUGCCACUUUCCAGUAUUUUUGAGCUUAUUUAAUGAGUUCUGGAACAUUUAUAUCUAAUCUAUAUUUUAGAUAAUUACUUUUUAUACUUUUUUAACUCAUGGUAUCCCCACUCCCCACCCCCACCUCAUUUUUAUUUGUCCCUUCUCAAAGCAGCCACUUAGCCCACAUGGGCGAAAUCAAGUCUCCAGUUAUUUCUGCCACAACUGCUUCUAAGGCCUCCUCCUUCUCCUCCUCCUCUUCCUCUUCCUCCUUUUCCUUCUCCUCCUCCUCUCUUCCCAGUGACAGCAUCAUCGUGCUGUUUGCCUGUAUUGGCUAUGCCUUCUAACUCCAACCAGUCACUUGAGAAUAUUCUUUCAAGAUUCUGGGCCCCGAUUCUUUUCUGUUUAAAUCCCUAAAGCAAAGAUCUAAUUCUCAAGCAAUGUCUGUAGUUCAGUGGGGGUGAACAAUGAAUAUAUUCAUGCUAGGAAUUUGUGUCUGUUGUUGUACUCACAGCAGCAACAUGAGUGUAAACAGUAGACAAUAAACUUUUAUUUAAGAAAACUGAUUCAGUUGUGUUGGAAAAAAUAAAGAAAUCUGAUAUUAAA